AGUACUUCCGUUCUCCAGCGCUGGGCACCGCGGCCGGAGCUGUGGGCUGGUAAGUCUGCGCCGCCAGGGCUCGCAUGGCCUUCAGAAGCGGUCCCUGGGCUGGGCGAUGACGGGUCCUGGUGGCAGCAGGCCCUUCUUUCUCGCAUCACCGGGCAUUACGCGGCAGCCAUUUCCCUCGCUAAGGCCCUACCUUAGGAUGACGUCACUUCCGGCCCCCUACUGUCUAGGGAAAGCCGGAAAUGGUACCAGCCUUCUUUGAUGGCGGGGAGGAGUCAAGACCGGUAGUCUUCCUAUUUCCGUUGUUUUGCUCUGGAGCCUCCCGGAGUUUCGGAGAGACCGUGUCUUGGAUAGAAUUGGAGGACUUAGCAAAUAAAAAUGCAAAGCGUCCAGUUACAUUUUUUUUGAGUUAGAAUCUCACUCUGUCACCCAGGCUGGAGUGCAGUGGCGCGAUCUCGGCUCACUGCAACCUCCGCCUCCCCUGUUCAAAUGAUUCUCAUGCCUCAGUCUCCCGAGUAGCUGGGAUUACGGGCGCCCACCACACCCGGCUAAUUUUUGUAUUUUUAGAAGAGACGGGGUUUCACCACGUUGGUCAGGCUGGUCUCGAACUCCUGACCUCAGGUGAUGCGCCCGCCUCAGCCUUCCAAAGUGCUGGGAUUACAGGCGUGAGCCACUGCGCCGGGCCACGUCCAGUUAAAUUUGAGUUAAGAUAAACGACGAAUAAUUGUUAAGUCCUAAACAUUGUAUGCACAUACUUAUACUUUAAAAAUUACUUGUUUAUUUGAAAUUCAAAUUUAACCGGAAGUCCUGUAUUUUCUCUGGCAGCCUUAGCAUUGAGCGUCCCCCUGUCCUGUGCUCAUACCCAGUGGCAAGGCUGGGAUCUUCUAGGCUCUUGUCCAUCUGGGAAAUAGAUACAAAUUUCAUCCAGGCUAUAAAGACCGGCUGUCUUAGUUGCUAAGAUGCUUUUAGCUCCAAGUCCAAUGGGCAAGCUCCAGGGGUCCCCCUGGCCAAAACUGGACCCAUUUUCGGAAUCCCCAUGACGAUGCCCUCUGUGUUCCCUUUCACAACAGAAGUCAGGCAUGGCUGUCUUUUCUUACCGGAGAGCUGAGAACUAGGCAAGCAAAAUGGUCAAAGUCUAGAAGUAACCACCAUAUUUGGGUGUGGGGUAAACCGGUGUUUGAGAUCUGUGUUGCAGUGGACAGUAUCAGAGAGCCUGAGGUUGUUAAGGGAAGAGCGUAGUGUUAAUCUCACCCCAUGUCUCAUUUUGCGGAUGAGGCCCAGUGAGAGAAAUGGAGGUGUCCCAGCCACUCAGAAAGCCUAUAGUAGAGCUGGAACCUCAAUUCCCAGCCUCCUUACCCUGCUCAGUCCAUACUUGCUGAUGAAGUCAGCUUGCAACAUUUAUGGUAGGCAUUUAUUAAAGUAGAUGCAAUAGUACAUAUGUAGUACAGAUGAGCUGUUUGGGUCUUUGUUGUUCCUAUACCCCUCUACAGCUUCCUGACCUUCGCCCCAAGGCUUCUUUAGCUUUUACUCUGCCCAGUGGGGAAAAUGGCUAUGGGCUCAGUUAUGGGAGCCUGGCCUUUGCCUACUUCAGCCCUUGGGCUCUCACCACUGUGGGUGGUGUGACCUAGGACUUGUUUUUGUUAUCUUGGAACCAGAAGGCGUGUUCUUGGCAGGGUUGGGUCUGGCCAACUGUGUGGGUAGAAGGGCAUCCUUUUCUGUCCUGCAAUUGGGCUUCAUGGCACAUGGCCUCACAUGGUGCCUGGGGACUUUUCUAAGGUUCCACCAUGAGCCAGACUUUGCCCUCACUCCUGAUUUGAACCUAAACCUCUUGCUGAACUGGUCCUGCAUACUGAGAUUCCUCAGAUUGCUUGCCCUGAGGAUGUGUUCUGGGUUUGACCUGAUAAACCUGCAGCCUCCUAUAGACCCUGACUUCCCAGGCUCCUAAUCCCAGUCUCAUGAGAUAAUGAAAUAGAGAAGACUGGAGGUCAAUGGGCUCAGGGUCAGUUGGUGGGACAAUCAACAGCUUCCUGGCAGCAGAGGUGGUAAAGAGGCAAGGAAGGAGUGCCAGAAAGGGGCGUUGCCCCAGGGUAACAGCGCAGAAGUGCAGGGGGUGGAAAAGGGGUGGGAUGGGAGCCCACUGGUAGAAAUUACUCCCUCUGUCAAUGAUUAACUCCCAGCCAAAGGGGUGACCUGGGAGGAGGGCCCAGCUAAUAGGAACUUUGGACUUGAGGCAGAGUAUCCAGAGGGCCGGCAUGUGGUCUGCAGAAGAGGAGGACGUGGCUGGGUGGCAGGGCUGGUCUCCAAGGACGAGUAAGAUCCUGCAGCUGCAGGCUUCAGGAAGUCUCCUGGGGCUAUCAGAUGGCUCCUUCUUGUAGCAGCAGCUGUGGGGUCCACUGGCCCUGAGCCCUCAGAGGGGCGGCCGUGGGGGACCUCCUGUCUUUUGCCUUGCAAGGGCCUCAGUUGUGCUUUUUCCCUCUAGGCAGCCAUGGGUGCCAGGCAGUGCUGAGAGCAGUGGGGCAUGGCUGCAGCCCUGCAGGUCCUGCCCCGCUUGGCCCGAGCCCCCUUGCAUCCACUCCUCUGGCGGGGCUCAGUGGCCCGUCUGGCCAGCAGCAUGGCCUUGGCAGAGCAGGCCAGGCAGCUGUUUGAGAGUGCUGUAGGUGCAGUGCUGCCGGGCCCCAUGCUGCACCGGGCACUAUCCUUGGACCCUGGUGGCAGACAGCUGAAGGUGCGGGACCGGAACUUUCAGCUGAGGCAAAACCUCUACCUGGUGGGCUUUGGCAAGGCUGUGCUGGGUAUGGCAGCUGCAGCUGAGGAACUACUGGGCCAGCAUCUUGUGCAGGGCGUGAUCAGCGUUCCCAAGGGGAUCCGUGCUGCCAUGGAGCGUGCCGGCAAGCAGGAGAUGCUGCUGAAGCCACAUAGCCGUGUCCAGGUAUUCGAGGGUGCGGAGGACAACCUCCCGGACCGCGAUGCGCUGCGGGCUGCACUGGCCAUCCAGCAACUGGCUGAGGGACUCACAGCUGAUGACCUGCUGCUCGUGCUGAUCUCAGGUGGGGGUUCAGCUCUGCUGCCUGCCCCCAUCCCACCUGUCACACUGGAGGAGAAGCAGACACUCACUAGACUGCUGGCAGCCCGUGGAGCCACCAUCCAGGAGUUGAACACCAUUCGGAAGGCCCUGUCCCAGCUCAAGGGUGGGGGGCUGGCUCAGGCCGCCUACCCUGCCCAGGUGGUGAGCCUCAUCCUGUCAGAUGUGGUGGGGGACCCUGUGGAGGUGAUUGCCAGUGGCCCCACCGUGGCCAGUUCCCACAAUGUGCAAGAUUGCCUGCAUAUCCUCAAUCGCUACGGCCUCCGUGCAGCCCUGCCACGUUCUGUGAAGACUGUGCUGUCUCGGGCCGACUCUGACCCCCAUGGGCCACACACCUGUGGCCAUGUCCUGAAUGUGAUCAUUGGCUCUAAUGUGCUGGCGCUAGCUGAGGCCCAGCGGCAGGCCGAGGCACUGGGCUACCAGGCUGUGGUGCUGAGUGCAGCCAUGCAAGGUGAUGUAAAAAGUAUGGCCCAGUUCUACGGGCUGCUGGCCCAUGUGGCUAGAACCCGCCUCACCCCAUCCAUGGCUGGGGCUUCUGUGGAGGAAGAUGCACAGCUCCAUGAGCUGGCAGCUGAGCUUCAGAUCCCAGACCUGCAGCUGGAGGAGGCUCUGGAGACCAUGGCAUGGGGAAGGGGCCCAGUCUGCCUGCUGGCUGGUGGCGAGCCCACAGUACAGCUGCAGGGCUCGGGCAGGGGUGGCCGGAACCAGGAACUGGCCCUGCGUGUUGGAGCAGAGUUGAGAAGGUGGCCGCUGGGGCCGAUAGAUGUGCUGUUUUUGAGCGGUGGCACCGAUGGGCAGGAUGGGCCCACAGAGGCUGCUGGGGCCUGGGUCACACCUGAGCUUGCCAGCCAGGCUGCAGCUGAGGGCCUGGACAUAGCCACCUUCCUAGCCCACAAUGACUCACAUACCUUCUUCUGCUGCCUCCAGGGUGGGGCACACCUGCUGCACACAGGGAUGACAGGUACCAAUGUCAUGGACACCCACCUCUUGUUCCUGCGGCCUCGGUGAUGGCAUAGGUCACAUUUUGGGAGUUCAGAGGAGGCCUACAAGGGCAAGGUCAGAUGGCAGAGCAAGGUUGGUCCUCAGGGCCUCUCUAAGCCUUAGGGCCCCUCCUCUCCUUGGCCUUGGCUGUUUGGUUAACUGUCACCUUCCACUCAGGGCCUCUGCUCUAUAUCUAUUCCCUUCCAGCCAGACUGGCAGAUGGGGGCUUCCCCCUACCCCUGAGGAUGAGGACAAGCCCCUCGGCCAGUUCAGCGUUCCCGUGCUUCUCCCUUGGGCAGCCUCUCUCUUGAGCCCCUCACCCUGUUUCUUUCUGUGAAGCGAGAAUGUCUGAAAAUAAAUAGGACCAUGCCAUGGGUUCUCAGUGCGCCUUCCCUCAGAGUGAGGCCUCACGGGGGAGCCGCUGGGAGGGGAGCGUGGUACGGCUGCAGCCACAGUACCAGGGCCUGGCAGGACUCUUAACACCCCUCUACUGGGCUGGGUACGUGCAGGAUGUGCCUCGCAUAACGGGAGCCUGUGCCCAUCCCUCUGGAGUGUGUGAGGGUUGAGCUUGGCUCCUGACAGCUUUGAUGUGCGUGAGCAGAGACCCCAGGGAGGACAGGCCUAAAGACUGCAGUCUGGGGUGACCAGCCACCCACCCACCCAACCAUGACUCCACCAUGGCACUGUCACCAUGGCUUCUCCAGCCUCAGCUUGUAGGCCUCGUUGGAUGGAUGUCCUUUCUGUCUUUGGACAGCCCUUAGCCACAUACUGCACUUCUGGUUGAGCUGAAGUUUGUCCCACCCCCCAGUGCUGUUUCCUUGUGACAGCCCUUGUCCUAGGCUGAACAUCCCUAGUUCCUUCAGCCACUCCUCUGGGGACCAAGUCCAGACCCUGAAGUCAGCCCUUCAGUGGGGGUCCCAGCACUGGGAUGGUGGGUCCAGCCAGUGAUGAGGUCCAGUGACCCACACCUCUUCCUGUGACCACUGGCGGGAGAAGAGGCAAGUGGGAAUAGAGGAACGGCUGUGUUGGCCUGGCCAGCAGCCUGGGUUGAGAGAGGGAGGUGCCACUGUCCUGCCUCCUUUUGAGCCCCCUUGCUCAGUGUCAGAACCCUCCGCUGGCUGUCCCCGCCGUGCGCCACGGCUCCAAUCCCUAUAUGAGUGAGCAGUAGAAUCACAUAGGAAUAAAAAGCCAUAGAGAACAGCGAGGCCUGGGGCUGCUCUUGCAGGCACUUCUUCCACCCCAACCCUCCCCUCCUCCCUGAGGGUGUGGAGGGGCCCUGGGCCAGGGCUGGCAGGACUUUCCCCUGGGAAGGGUUUCCCUUCCCCACCUGGGCUCUGGGCAGCCUAGCUUGCAGACAGUUCAUGACCUGGGGGCCUGGCUCACACAGGGCAGGCUGGAGAUUGGGAGGGAGGUAAACGUGGUAAGCGGGCUCUGGGGACCAGGGAGGUUUAGGAAAAGGGGAGCUUGCACCCCACUGGGAUGCGCAGGCACCGCUUCCUUUCCUUCUGUGCUGGCAUGGAGUUCCUGCUGACUAGGGUCACAGUCUCUGGGGUUAUGGUGAUCCUCGCAUGAUCCUGUGCCGUGGUGCUCCUCUGGCAGCGUCUACAUGUAGCCUGUUCCUGCCUCAGUCCUUGCUCUUGGGAGCAUGAGUAUUGGCACUGGGUUCCAAGUUCCAGGCAAAAGCAGGAUAGGAGAGCUGGGGCAGGGGCUGCAGGAGCUGAGGGCCUGGCAGCCAUGUCCCCAGUGUGUGUGUGGGUGGUAGGUGUGUGAGUAUACAGACGUUGGUGUUGGCGUACUCAGAGUGGGAAUGCAUCUCUGAGUGUACACAUAGAUACUUAGUACAGGGCACAUGACUCCCUGCAUCCCUGCUGAGGGCUUUGGGUAUGGAUAGGAUCUUGCAGGAGGUUCCCCCUGCUCUACAUUGACCCCUUCCCUAUACUUCUGUUUGUAGGGGCUGGGAGGCCAGGGCCCGGAUUGGACCCCAUAGGGCCAAAUGGUCUGUGAGCCUAACCCGUUAGAUUUGCUCACUGGAUACCCCAGAGAUAAGAAAGGAUGUAUUUGGCCACAGUCUAAAUGCUGAGAUGAGAAAACCCUGCACAGUGAAUGUUUUGAUAGGAUUCAUUACUUGCUCCAUAAAUGUCAAUUUUGGAUCAUUGAA